GGAGCUGGGAGCAGUUAGGAAGGGCUUUCCUGGGGAAGUGGUGCUUGGGACACCUGAGGCUGAUUCUCCCAGCAACCAUUAGUUAAGCACCCACUGUGUAUCAGCCACUGUGAAACUGUGUAAGUUGCUGGGGUAAGACAGGUGCCCCACCCUCUGGGCUCACAGCCUCCAGUAGGUGAUAAAAAGGUAUGUGGGGUCAGGUGCAGUGGCUCAUACCUGUAAUCCCAGAACUUUGGGAGGCUGAGGCGGGCAGAUCACUUGAGCCCAGGAGUUCAAUACUAGGCUGGGCAGCAUAGCAAGACCCCGUCUCUAUAAAAAAUAAAAAGUUAAUUGGGUGUGGUGGCACACACCUGUAGUCCCAGCUACCCAGGAGGCUGAGGUGAGAGGAAUGCUUGAGCCGGGGAGAUUGAGGCUGAGUAAGCUGUGAUCUUGCCACUGCACUCCAGCCUGGGUGACUCAAUGAGACCCUGCCUCAAAAAAACACAAAAAAACAAAAAACAAAAGCCAGUAGGUGGUUCCAUUAGAUCGUGAUAAGUGAUGAGAUAGGGAGGGGGCAGAUGUCCUGCAGAAGGUGAUAUCUGAGCUUCAUUUCGAAAGCAUCCCUGUUCAACCUUUGUCCCCUCGGCCUCACCUUGAGGAAGGAGGAAGCAAGAAACCCAGCAGGCAGAGCGCAGAGAAGCCCGGUGAAGGCAAAGGGCUUCCGACACUUAUUCAUUCAGCAAACACUGAGUGCCUACUGUAUGCCAGGCCCCGAAAGCACAGCAGCAAACAGAGCCCCUGCCCUCAUGGGGACACAGCCCAGCCAGAGACAGGCAAGGAAACCACCACAGGCAUCAUAUAGACUUGUGUCUCUGAGCUGUGUGUGUGGCAAGGGCGCUGAGUGGGACUCGGCCUGGCUAGGGCCGGCUUCCCUGGGGACUGGAGGGGUGAGGAGCCUUUUCUGGCCCAGGCAAGGGAUGCAGCUUCUGGCGGAGGCCUGUGUAGGGGCUGUGCAAGACCUCAGUUUCCUCAUCUGGCACACCGUAGGAAAUAAAUGUGCCCUGAUCACACUUGCUUCCAGGCGGCCUGCGUCCUGGCCUGCAGCCCUCGAAAAGAAGGCGCUGUCGCUUCCAGUGGAAGGUGGCGACCUCUCCAGGCCGGGCCGGGCUCGGCACUCGGAGCGAGUGCGGCAACCACUGUCGCUCUCCGAAGGCUCCUGCGCCCCCCGGGGCAGCUGGGCGGGGUAAUGCCCUCAGUGAUGGAGAAGCCGAGCGCGGGCUCUGGGAUCCUGUCCCGUAGCCGGGCCAAGACGGUGCCCAACGGCGGACAGCCCCACUCGGAGGAUGACAGCAGCGAGGAGGAGCACUCGCACGACAGCAUGAUCCGCGUUGGAACCAAUUACCAGGCCGUAAUUCCGGAGUGCAAGCCUGAGAGCCCCGCACGCUACAGCAACAAGGAGCUGAAGGGGAUGCUGGUGUGGUCACCCAACCACUGUGUGUCAGAUGCCAAGCUUGACAAGUACAUUGCGAUGGCCAAGGAGAAGCAUGGCUACAACAUUGAGCAGGCGCUGGGCAUGCUUCUGUGGCAUAAGCACGAUGUGGAGAAGUCGCUGGCCGACCUGGCCAACUUCACCCCAUUCCCUGACGAGUGGACAGUAGAGGACAAGGUGCUGUUUGAACAGGCCUUUGGCUUCCAUGGCAAAUGCUUCCAGCGGAUCCAGCAGAUGCUGCCUGACAAGUUGAUUCCCAGCCUGGUGAAAUACUACUACUCUUGGAAGAAGACCCGCAGCCGAACUAGUGUGAUGGACAGACAGGCCCGGCGGCUGGGGGGCCGCAAGGACAAAGAAGACAGUGAUGAGCUCGAAGAGGGUCGAGGAGGCGUGAGUGAGGGAGAGCCCGAUCCUGCAGAUCCCAAGAGAGAGCCUCUACCCUCUCGGCCCCUGAAUGCACGCCCAGGCCCUGGGAAAAAGGAGGUCCAGGUGUCUCAGUACCGCCACCAUCCCUUGCGAACCCGGCGUCGCCCACCCAAGGGCAUGUACCUGAGCCCUGAAGGCCUCACGGCAGUGUCAGGAAGCCCGGACCUUGCCAACCUCACGCUCCGAGGUCUUGACUCUCAGCUCAUCUCCCUCAAGCGCCAGGUACAGAGCAUGAAGCAGACGAACAGCAGCCUGCGCCAAGCCCUGGAGGGCGGUAUUGAUCCACUACGCCCCCCGGAGGCCAACACCAAGUUCAACUCCCGCUGGACCACAGAUGAGCAGCUUUUGGCUGUUCAAGCCAUCCGUAGGUAUGGCAAAGACUUUGGGGCUAUUGCAGAGGUGAUUGGGAACAAGACUCUGACCCAGGUGAAGACUUUCUUUGUGAGCUACCGGCGCCGCUUCAAUCUGGAGGAGGUGCUGCAGGAAUGGGAGGCUGAGCAGGAUGGGGCCCCUGGAGCCCCAGUCCCCAUGGAGGAGGCUAGGAGAGGGGCUCCAUUGCCAGCCCCAGCCCUAGAGGAAGAUGAUGAGGUCCAGAUUACAUCGGUCUCCACGUCCGUGCCCCGAUCAGUGCCCCCUGCGCCACCACCCCCUCCACCUCCCACCUCGCUGUCCCAGCCACCCCCGCUGCUGAGGCCACCUUUGCCCACGGCUCCCACUCUGCUCCGACAGCCACCCCCACUGCAGCAGGGCCGCUUCCUCCAGCCCCGGCUGGCCCCCAACCAGCCCCCACCGCCUCUCAUCCGCCCCGCUCUGGCUGCCCCCCGCCACAGCGCCCGCCCUGGCCCUCAGCCCCCACCCACCCUGAUUGGAACCCCUCUGGAGCCCCCAGCACCCUCACUCUGAGCCCUGACGUCCUCCACCAACCACGGGCUCCAGGACCCCUUUGCUGGCCAUCCCCAGGCAUCUCUGGUGUCACUGAGGACAGAAGGGACUAGGGCUCUGGCGGGGUCUUUGUAAGACCAGAGUUUCGGACAGCCCAGCCCCGCCCUUUGGGUUCUGCAUGUGUUCCUGGCAGCUGGGCCUGUCUCCUGGGGCCAUGGCCGGGCUCAGGGGCCUUUGAGCUGGCCUGAGGGCACUUUCGCUUCCUGGCCGGUACUGGAAUGGCUGUGUCCUAGUCUGCUGGGGCUUGGCCUCUGGGUCCUGCCCUUUGUGUGUCCGGGGUAGUGACCUUAGCGUGGAGUGGGGAGAGGGCAGUUGGGUGUGCUGGCUGUUCUCAUUCCUCUUUCCCUUCUUUUAGCAAUAAGUCUGGGGUGAGGUGGGGAGGGAGGCUGCAGGGGGGGAGGUGGGCAGAGGGGCCUUACAGCAGCAGAGGCUGGAAGAGAAGCUCUGUCUUCAGGGGCCAGCUGGGAAAUGCUAAGGAGCUGAGGGUGCCCACCAAGCCCACCUUCCAGAAACUUGGAGAAAUGGGGGUUGGGAACUUAUGCAGACAUGGAUUUAUUUUUCAACAUUUUUUAAAAAUUAAAAAAAAUAAAAUCUAA